AGGGCGGAGCGCAGCUGCGCCGGGCUUGGGCGCCUGGGGCCGCCGCUCCCCACCGUCGUUUUCCCCACCGAGGCCGAGGCGUCCCGGAGUCAUGGCCGGCCUGAACUGCGGGGUCUCUAUCGCACUGCUAGGGGUUCUGCUGCUGGGUGCGGCGCGCCUGCCGCGCGGGGCAGAUGAGGAAAGUGAGGCACCAAGAAGCUAAGGAAUUUGCCCAAGGAAGCACAUCUGGAAGCUUUUGAGAUUGCUCUGCCACGAGAAAGCAACAUUACAGUUCUCAUAAAGCUGGGGACCCCGACUCUGCUGGCAAAACCCUGUUACAUCGUCAUUUCUAAAAGACAUAUAACCAUGUUGUCCAUCAAGUCUGGAGAAAGAAUAGUCUUUACCUUUAGCUGCCAGAGUCCUGAGAAUCACUUUGUCAUAGAGAUCCAGAAAAAUAUUGACUGUAUGUCAGGCCCAUGUCCUUUUGGGGAGGUUCAGCUUCAGCCCUCGACAUCGUUGUUGCCUACCCUCAACAGAACUUUCAUCUGGGAUGUCAAAGCUCAUAAGAGCAUCGGUUUAGAGCUGCAGUUUUCCAUCCCUCGCCUGAGGCAGAUCGGUCCGGGUGAGAGCUGCCCAGACGGAGUCACUCACUCCAUCAGCGGCCGAAUCGAUGCCACCGUGGUCAGGAUCGGAACCUUCUGCAGCAAUGGCACUGUGUCCCGGAUCAAGAUGCAAGAAGGAGUGAAAAUGGCCUUACACCUCCCAUGGUUCCACCCCAGAAAUGUCUCCGGCUUCAGCAUUGCAAACCGCUCAUCUAUAAAACGUCUGUGCAUCAUCGAGUCUGUGUUUGAGGGUGAAGGCUCAGCAACCCUGAUGUCUGCCAACUACCCAGAAGGCUUCCCUGAGGAUGAGCUCAUGACGUGGCAGUUUGUCGUUCCUGCACACCUGCGGGCCAGCGUCUCCUUCCUCAACUUCAACCUCUCCAACUGUGAGAGGAAGGAGGAGCGGGUUGAAUACUACAUCCCGGGCUCCACCACCAACCCCGAGGUGUUCAAGCUGGAGGACAAGCAGCCUGGGAACAUGGCGGGGAACUUCAACCUCUCUCUGCAAGGCUGUGACCAAGAUGCCCAAAGUCCAGGGAUCCUCCGGCUGCAGUUCCAAGUUUUGGUCCAACAUCCACAAAAUGAAAGCAAUAAAAUCUACGUGGUUGACUUGAGUAAUGAGCGAGCCAUGUCACUCACCAUCGAGCCACGGCCCGUCAAACAGAGCCGCAAGUUUGUCCCUGGCUGUUUCGUGUGUCUAGAAUCUCGGACCUGCAGUAGCAACCUCACCCUGACAUCUGGCUCCAAACACAAAAUCUCCUUCCUUUGUGAUGAUCUGACACGUCUGUGGAUGAAUGUGGAAAAAACCAUAAGCUGCACAGACCACCGGUACUGCCAAAGGAAAUCCUACUCACUCCAGGUGCCCAGUGACAUCCUCCACCUGCCUGUGGAGCUGCAUGACUUCUCCUGGAAGCUGCUGGUGCCCAAGGACAGGCUCAGCCUGGUGCUGGUGCCAGCCCAGAAGCUGCAGCAGCAUACACACGAGAAGCCCUGCAACACCAGCUUCAGCUACCUCGUGGCCAGUGCCAUACCCAGCCAGGACCUGUACUUCGGCUCCUUCUGCCCGGGAGGCUCUAUCAAGCAGAUCCAGGUGAAGCAGAACAUCUCGGUGACCCUUCGCACCUUUGCCCCCAGCUUCCAACAAGAGGCCUCCAGGCAGGGUCUGACGGUGUCCUUUAUACCUUAUUUCAAAGAGGAAGGCGUUUUCACGGUGACCCCUGACACAAAAAGCAAGGUCUACCUGAGGACCCCCAACUGGGACCGGGGCCUGCCAUCCCUCACCUCUGUGUCCUGGAACAUCAGCGUGCCCAGAGACCAGGUGGCCUGCCUGACUUUCUUUAAGGAGCGGAGCGGCGUGGUCUGCCAGACAGGGCGCGCAUUCAUGAUCAUCCAGGAGCAGCGGACCCGGGCUGAGGAGAUCUUCAGCCUGGACGAGGAUGUGCUCCCCAAGCCAAGCUUCCACCAUCACAGCUUCUGGGUCAACAUCUCUAACUGCAGCCCCACGAGCGGCAAGCAGCUAGACCUGCUCUUCUCGGUGACACUUACCCCAAGGACUGUGGACUUGACUGUCAUCCUCAUCGCAGCGGUGGGAGGUGGAGUCUUACUGCUGUCUGCCCUCGGGCUCAUCAUUUGCUGUGUGAAAAAGAAGAAAAAGAAGACAAACAAGGGCCCCGCUGUGGGUAUCUACAAUGACAACAUCAAUACUGAGAUGCCGAGGCAGCCAAAAAAGUUUCAGAAAGGGCGAAAGGACAAUGACUCCCAUGUGUAUGCAGUCAUCGAGGACACCAUGGUAUAUGGGCAUCUGCUACAGGAUUCCAGCGGCUCCUUCCUGCAGCCAGAGGUGGACACCUACCGGCCGUUCCAGGGCACCAUGGGGGUCUGUCCUCCCUCCCCACCCACCAUAUGCUCCAGGGCCCCAACUGCAAAGUUGGCCACUGAGGAGCCACCUCCUCGCUCCCCUCCUGAGUCUGAGAGUGAACCGUACACCUUCUCCCAUCCCAACAAUGGGGAUGUAAGCAGCAAGGACACAGACAUUCCCUUACUGAACACUCAGGAGCCCAUGGAGCCAGCAGAAUAACUUGAUCCAUUCCAGACGCUUUGCUGAGUUUCAUAAAGCAGGGCACUGAGACACCCGUCCGUGUUCCUAACCAGAAAUCCUAAAGAAGAGGAAUUAUACAGAAGGAACAGCAGGAGGUUUUCCUGGACACCGCCAACUUCACAUUGCUCAGUGGACUCAUUCUAAGGGCAAGACAUUGAAAAUGAUGAAUUCCAAUCUGGAUACAGUCAUGACAGCUCAUGUGCUCCUCAACUUAGGCUGUGCGGUUAGCCAGCCUGUAAUGAGAGGAGAGAGGCCUGAGUCACCUAGCAUAGGGUUGCAGCAAGCCCUGGAUUCAGAGUGUUAAACAGAGGCUUGCCCUCUUCAGGACAACAGUUCCAAUUCCAAGGAGCCUACCUGAGGUCCCUACUCUCACUGGGGUCCCCAGGAUGAAAACGACAAUGUGCCUUUUUAUUAUUAUUUAUUUGGUGGUCCUGUGUUAUUUAAGAGAUCAAAUGUAUAACCACCUAGCUCUUUUCACCUGACUUAGUAAUAACUCAUACUAACUGGUUUGGAUGCCUGGGUUGUGACUUCUACUGACCGCUAGAUAAACGUGUGCCUGUCCCCCAGGUGGUGGGAAUAAUUUACAAUCUGUCCAACCAGAAAAGAAUGUGUGUGUUUGAGCAGCAUUGACACAUAUCUGCUUUGAUAAGAGACUUCCUGAUUCUCUAGGUCGGUUCGUGGUUAUCCCAUUGUGGAAAUUCAUCUUGAAUCCCAUUGUCCUAUAGUCCUAGCAAUAAGAGAAAUUUCCUCAAGUUUCCAUGUGCGGUUCUCCUAGCUGCAGCAAUACUUUGACAUUUAAAGAGAAAUUUAGAGAAUAUUCUCAUCCUCUAAAAAUGUUUAAAUAUAUACCAAACAGUGGCCCCCUGCAUUAGUUUUCUGUUGCCACUGCAACCUAUUACUUGGUAGCUUAAAAACAACACAUUAGCUUAUAGUCCUGGGGAUCAGAAUUCCAAAAUGGAUGUCCCUGAAUGAAAAUCAAGGUGUCAGCAGAGCUGUGCUCCUUCUGAAGGCUCUAGGGAGAAGCCGGUUCCUUGCCAUUUCAAGCUUCUAGAGGCUGGCUGCAUUCCCAGGCUCCAGUGGCUGGUCAAGCUUUUCUCACAUGGCAUCACUGUGACACUGGCCCUCCCACUUCCCUCUUUGACUUACAAAGCCCACCAGGAAGAUCCAGGAUAAUCUCUCCAUCUAAAGUUCCUUCAUCAUCCUGGAAGAGCCUUUUGCCAUGCAAGACAACAUAGCCACAGGUGGGGAUUAGGACCAGAACAUCUUUGGGGUGCUGUUAUUCUGCCUACCACACCUUCCUGCCACUGACUCCCACAGGAGAGGCUACAAAAUGAUCUGGCGCACAGGGAUGUUUUGUUUAGCUUGCGGACUCUAACACUUAAAAAAAAACCCAGAUCAGAAGAUCUGGCCAUGCUGGGGCUCACAUUCUCACCUAGCAACAACUGGCUGGAGCUGGGCACCAGCUCUGCCUUUAGAAGGGGUGUCCACUUCACCAGGUCACCACAGCCCACACUACGCCCUAUCACUUCCCACAAUGAGGCUGAGUGUUUGUUUCUACUGAUCAAUGCCCCUGCAGGUUGCAUUUAUUGUAAUGAAAAAGAAAGACUGGGAUUAAUCUCUAAUCAGGUGAGUAGACCAUGAGACCAAUGUGUGCUCACAUUACCCUUUUUCUUUUUUUUCUUUUUCUUUUUCUUUUUUUUUUUAAUGUGAGACAGGAUCUCAUUCUGUUGCCUAGGCUGGAGUGCAGUGGCGCAAUCUCGGCUCACUGCAACCUCUGCCUCCUGGGCUCAAGCAAUUCUCCCACCUCAGCCUCCCAAAUAGCUGGGAUCACUGGCACAAACCACCAUGCCCAGCUAAUUUUGUAUUUUUUGUAGAGACAGGGUUUCACCAUGUUGCCCAGGCUGGUCUCAACCUCCUGGGCUCAAGCAAUCCUCCUGCCUCGGCCUCCCAAAGUGCUGGGAUUACAGAUGUGAGCCACCGCAUCCAGCCCCACACCCUCAUUUAUACCAAUUACCUGCCCAGUAACUGUGGACUUUUGCUUCCUCACCCCUGCUCUGAUCUGGAAGGAGAGGGAUUAUGUUAUAGCUUGUCAGCACAGUCCCAAGUUCAAUAUUUCUGCGGCAAAAACUUCCUUCAAAAAAUAAAUGUACUUCAUUGUAUUCAAUGAAUUCACCUUGGAAAUGCACCGCCUCAACUUGUUCACAUGGCAUAAAUGAAAGGAAUUUUAUAGUCUCCUAAAUGGCGUGUACUGCAAGACCUCUUGAACACUUUCCAGAGGAUAGGAUAUUUAAGUCAUGCCCUUGGCGUUGCCUAUGGCACCUUUCCCUUCUGAAAGUCUGGUUCCUGCCCAGUGACCCUUGGCCUUGUGAGCCGAGAUGCUGACCCUGCAUAAAGGGCCAAAGGAGGGCUGCGGCUUCCUUCCCUCACUGAAGAGCCCUUAUUUGAAUUCACUGUGUGGAGCCCUAGCCCUCCAUUCUCGACAUUCCCCAACCUCCCAGCCCCUUCCAAGCAGGACUAGGUGCCCUGCAUUCCACCCAAGGUGGGAUUGGCCUUCCUUAGGCUGGCUACUUGUCACCAUCACCGACAUCACUGUUGCCUGCAAGGACACCACGUGGCCAUUUUCCUUCAACUGAGGGCUCAAAACUCCUGGACAAGUUGCUGGCUCCUGAGACCAGUAUUUCCUGGAGCUGUGCCUCAGUGAAGGGGCCCAGCCUGAGGAACCCUGGCUCUUUUCUUUAAAGCCCAGGCCCCACUUACGUAAAACAUUUCAGGGUCACUGGAAACAGUGAAGUGCCAUUUGUUGAAGCCUACUGCAUGCCAGCCCACUGCUCAUCCACGUGGUCUGCCAUGCCUACGAGGAAGGCCAGCGCAUGCAGGACUGGUCUCUAAUGCUGUGGUCAUUGCACAGAAGGGAAAGGUCUCAAGGAAGAGUCAACUGGAACAAGCACAAGCCCACCGGACAUGGCCUUGGUAAAGGUUAGCAGACUGGUGUGUGUGGAUCUGCAGUGCUUCACUGGAAAUAAUUUAUUCAUUGCAGAUACUUUUUAGGUGGCAUUUUAUUCAUUUCCUGUGCUUUAAAUAAACAAAUGUACCAAAAAACAAGUAUCAAGCUGUUUAAGUGCUUCGGCUACUUGUCCCCUGGUUCAGUAGAGGCCCCGGUUUCCCAGUUGUUGACUGUGACAGGCUCAGCAUGGGCUCAGCAGAUGCUGUCUUAAUUUGUGGAUGAUACAGAAAGCCAGGCUUUGGGAUACAAGUUCUUUCCUCUUCAUUUGAUGCCGUGCACUGUGUGAAGCAGAUGUUUUUGUCCGGAAAUAAAAAUAAUAGUCUUGGAGUCUCGCCA